AGUGAGGACUUCUCUGCUCCAUGCAUGCACCACCUUUCACUUAUUAUUUAUAUUUUUACAUCUUUAUUUUAGUUUCUGCCUCCUCCACAUAGAAUGUAAGUUCUAUCAUGGCAAUAUUUUUUUUUUUUUGUAUUAUUGUAUCCUCAUUGCCUACAGCUGAGUUAGGCACAGAGAAUGCAUGCAGCACAUGUUUGUUGAAUGAAUGACUCCUUGUAGAAAAUGAAAGCCCGAAAAUAAGCCGACUGGUUCCCCGAGAGAGAAGAAACUCAAAUCUGCCCAUCCUCAUAAAGGAGCAAACCUGUCUUUUAAGCUAAGGCCUUUUUCCUGUGUUCAUACUUCAGAAAAAGAAGACACGACUGAUAACAUCUGAGAGGAAGGAAACUGCAUUGUGCUGGGGAUCUGCAUGUCACAUUAUAAAAAGCAAUUUUUUUUUUUAAUAGAACCAGCCUUUCAAACAGUUUCCAGAGAUGGAUUAUCCUACUUUACUUUUGGCUCUUCUUCAUGUAUACAGAGCUCUAUGUGAAGAGGUGCUUUGGCAUACAUCAGUUCCCUUUGCCGAGAACAUGUCUCUAGAAUGUGUGUAUCCAUCAAUGGGCAUCUUAACACAGGUGGAGUGGUUCAAGAUCGGGACCCAGCAGGAUUCCAUAGCCAUUUUCAGCCCUACUCAUGGCAUGGUCAUAAGGAAGCCCUAUGCUGAGAGGGUUUACUUUUUGAAUUCAACGAUGGCUUCCAAUAACAUGACUCUUUUCUUUCGGAAUGCCUCUGAAGAUGAUGUUGGCUACUAUUCCUGCUCUCUUUACACUUACCCACAGGGAACUUGGCAGAAGGUGAUACAGGUGGUUCAGUCAGAUAGUUUUGAGGCAGCUGUGCCAUCAAAUAGCCACAUUGUUUCGGAACCUGGAAAGAAUGUCACACUCACUUGUCAGCCUCAGAUGACGUGGCCUGUGCAGGCAGUGAGGUGGGAAAAGAUCCAGCCCCGUCAGAUCGACCUCUUAACUUACUGCAACUUGGUCCAUGGCAGAAAUUUCACCUCCAAGUUCCCAAGACAAAUAGUGAGCAACUGCAGCCACGGAAGGUGGAGCGUCAUCGUCAUCCCCGAUGUCACAGUCUCAGACUCGGGGCUUUACCGCUGCUACUUGCAGGCCAGCGCAGGAGAAAACGAAACCUUCGUGAUGAGAUUGACUGUAGCCGAGGGUAAAACCGAUAACCAAUAUACCCUCUUUGUGGCUGGAGGGACAGUUUUAUUGUUGUUGUUUGUUAUCUCAAUUACCACCAUCAUUGUCAUUUUCCUUAACAGAAGGAGAAGGAGAGAGAGAAGAGAUCUAUUUACAGAGUCCUGGGAUACACAGAAGGCACCCAAUAACUAUAGAAGUCCCAUCUCUACCAGUCAACCUACCAAUCAAUCCAUGGAUGAUACAAGAGAGGAUAUUUAUGUCAACUAUCCAACCUUCUCUCGCAGACCAAAGACUAGAGUUUAAGCUUAUUCUUGACAUGAGUGCAUUAGUAAUGACUCUUAUGUACUCAUGCAUGGAUCUUUAUGCAAUUUUUUUCCACUACCCAAGGUCUACCUUAGAUACUAGUUGUCUGAAUUGAGUUACUUUGAUAGGAAAAAUACUUCAUUACCUAAAAUCAUUUUUCAUAGAACUGUUUCAGAAAACCUGACUCUAACUGGUUUAUAUACAAAAGAAAACUUACUGUAUCAUAUAACAGAAUGAUCCAGGGGAGAUUAAGCUUUGGGCAAGGGCUAUUUACCAGGGCUUAAAUGUUGUGUCUAGAAUUAAGUAUGGGCAUAAACUGGCUUCUGAAUCCCUUUCCAGAGUGUUGGAUCCAUUUCCCUGGUCUUGGCCUCACUCUCAUGCAGGCUUUCCUCUUGUGUUGGCAAGAUGGCUGCCAACUCUUGGCAAUUCAUACAUCCUUGUUUCUGUCUGGUAGAGAGUUUGCUUCUCAAAUGGAGCAAACAAAUUUGAUUAUUUUUUCAUUGUUAAAUAGGCAACAUGACCAGAAAGGAUGGAAUGGCUUAAGUAAACUAAGGGUUCACUUCUAGAGCUGAGAAGCAGGGUCAAAGCACAAUACUGGGCAAUUCAGAGCAUGGUUAGAAGAGGAAAGGGGAGUCUCAAAGCUGGAGAGUUUACCAACAAAUAUUGACUGCAGUGAUUAACCAAGACAUUUUUGUUAACUAAAAAGUGAAAUAUGGGAUGGAUUCUAGAAAUGGGGUAUCUCUGUCCAUACUUCUAGAAUCCACUCUAUCAGCAUAGUCCAGAAGAAUACCUGGCAGUAGAAGAAAUGAAUAUUCAAGAGGAAGAUAAAUGCGAGAGGGCAAUCCUUUACUAUUCUCAUAUUUAUUUAUCUCUCAUUCUGUAUAGAAUUCUUGCCGCCAUCCCAGGUCUAGCCUUAGGAGCAAAUGUAGUAGAUAGUCGAAUAAUAAAUAACUUAAUGUUUUGGACAUAUUUUGUCUACUUUUGAGAAUUAUUUUUAAUAUGUAAAUUCUCUCAAAAGGGUCAGGCACCUAGUUAUUAUUUUUUAAUGAUUAUGUGAAAGUUGAAUAUAAUAUACCACUAAAAGUGACAGUUGAAAGUGGUGGCAUAGGACGGUAGGGUAGAAAUUUGGGAGGGAAAAAAGAAAUUGGGAGGGUACAGGCAACAGGAGAAAGGAAUCAAACCACAGAAAAAUACAAAGGGAAACUUCUGCUUCACUAUUCAGACAAAGACAGCCCUAAUGACAUCACCAACAGUCAAAGCAAUUAGAGACCAUACCUAAUAUUGUUUAAAUUCUAGAUGUAGGCUAACAAUGAAAAGUAUUUGCCAAACUGAAUAAAACUGUCAUGGUUACCUUGAAAGGACAAUGGUUAUUGUUAAAUAUAGUGAUCAUUCAUGUCUAAAAGAUUCAUUAUUUAUCUCUAAAGAUUUCUAAAGACCACCAUCUAGAAAAGAUUCAUUAUGAAGGCUGUAUUUAAAUAUCAAAGUUGUGGACUUCAUGAUAAUCUUAAAUAAAGCAAAUCCAAAUUCUCCUGUUGCCUAGACAGAUUCUAAGAUGUAAUUUACACUUUUAAGCUAAUUAGUGAGUAUUUUAUGAUUUUAGCCUUAAACACCAUGUAUGCCAAAUAAUGCACUUGUUUUGUGAAUUACAGAAAUGGUAAGUGCCCACAUUUCUGUGAAUUAUAAAAUUUGUGAGUUUCUUUUAACCCUUUUCAGGAGUGAAAAAAUAAAAACGACCAUUUCCUGGUUGUGCUUAAGUAUAUGCAAGAAGGGUAAACUCUCAUUUUUAUUAUGUUUGCUUAAAGAUCUUUUUAUACCUGGAUUCAUGAAAUGUUUCCACAAAUAUAUUAGUGUAACAAACUUGAAAGGCAGUUUACAAGAAAGCACUCUACUAUCAGAUCAAUCAAAGAUUCUGUGAGUGAAUUUAUUGGUUUGCAUGGUGAAGCAAGCUUAGCAUCAAUUAAAAGGUAAAUAAUUUCUUUUCUGAAUGGUAAAGACAAUCAAAAUAUUACUUUCUGGAAAACUCCAAUAACCAAAUUCUCAAUGAUUAGUGUAUGUGAGCAGGAAAACAUUUUUACAGUUGUAGUAUGGGGAAAUAUAAAUCCAAUUUUAAGAGAGAAAAUUAUGACUGGGUGUGGAAGGGACAGUAUAGUCAGAUACCAUUGUCAUGGUGGUUUUUACUGGGAACUUCAUGAAAGACUUUUGUAGCAAACCACUGCAGUAUUGCAAAGCCUCCAGAACAUUUGGAACUUGUCUCUUUUUCCUUGUGUGUGUUUGUGUUUUUGGUCUCUCAUUCAAAAUAUUGAUGAGAACUAUUUACUCUGUCCUUUCUUCUCUAUAUAUUCUUCCUCUACAGAGUGUAGGGUUUUUUCAGGAAUUUGGAGCCAUCUGAAGUCCUCCCAAAAAUUCUCUGACGUCUUCUGAUGCUCCUGUUAUACCCUCAGGGGUAAUGCUUGUGAAAUUCCAUUCAUUCAUUUUCUUUCUCUGGACAUCUUUACUUACCAAAGCACUUUCAUUGUCAUCUUUUUAACAUCAUUCUUAAUUCGUGAUAGUUUUGGGACUCUCCCUAGUGUAUGUUUCUCCCCCUCUACUCUUUUGCACCUAUGAUUCUGAUUGUUACUAAGAAAGCAGAUGAAAAACAGAUCCACAGAAUAAACGAUCAGAAUUCCAGUAAAUUCUAUUUUAAAUACAGAUACUUUUUACAAGUUGCUGCUUUGGAAGCAAAAUGCUUCUUAAGUUUUACAUAUAUAUAUAUAUAUAUACAUAUAUAUAUACACAUAUAAUUUAUAUCGAUGGAUAAUACAUUAAGAAUCUAUGCUUCCUUUGAAUGCCAUUAAUAUUUAUGUUAAAGUAACCAAUGAAAGGAAAUUACUUUGUUAUAAUAAGAUAGGAAGACUUGUUAAUGGAGUACACAGUUUUGUCAGGGAAAGAACACAUCUUAUUGAACUAUGAUGACUAUGCAUUGACUAUAUUAUUAUAAGAGAUACCUUCAAACUUUAUUUAAAGAACUUUAGGUAUAAUAUGUUGAGAAAAUAAAAUAGAAAUUUCAUUUACUUGUAAUCAUGCUUAAAAUGGGAGGCAGGUAGGUGAAGAUAUAAUUUUUAGUAAAAACUCCAAUUUAUGUUUUAAGUAAUUCAGUGUAUUACUAAAAUACUAUAUAUAUAAACUUAAAAUACAUGGGUUAUCAAUUUAAAAGACAAAGUAAGUAAAAAUACUUUUAGUAGGCAUUCGUGGAUUGUGAACAUCCAAGUUAUAUUGGUUUGUAUAGAAUGGCAUUAAGUAAAAAUUACAGCUGUAUAACAGUAGUUUUCUAAAUUGAGAGAGUCCACAUUGUAAUUAGAGAUCACUGUGACCAAAAUGCUUCUCCUUGAUUUAUAAUGAUGUACUGUAUUUUGUACUGCUUAUAUGAAAUUUCAGCAAGAUUGACGAUAUUAUAAAGAUGCUUAUAAAGUGUAAGUGGAGACGCUAAAUUGUGAGUACAAAGUUUCUUUUUCACAACAGUGAUAAGAAAAUAUCUUUAAAAAAUAUAAGACAAUAUAAACAUGUCAUCAUUAGUUUAGCUACUAUUAAAAUGUAACAUCUAGAAAGUACUGAUCUCCACCUUCAGACUUCUGUAUAAGUAUAUUUUUUCACUGAUCUGUUCAUUAGAGUUCUUCCAGCCAAGACUCUGGGCUCUUAAAACAUGUAUCUGAAAACUAAAAACAAGUUAAUUUUUUUAAAAGCUUCUCUAUUUCUAGUGAUUCAAUAGGUAGAAAAAUAGCUUCUAGAAUUAACUGCAAUGCUUUCUAAGGAAAUUUUAUAAAUCCUCAAGGUCGGUUUACACAUAUUUUUCCAGAUUCAGAGCACUAACUAUCUUGUAAGAUGUAAGAAAAGGUCCAUUUGGAAGUAUGAGUAAUAAAUGUCUGGGAUAAUUCUGGUUUAUUUCGUAUUAUCCUUGUUAGAAUAAGUUAUAUGGUCAACCUGUUCAGAACACUUUUUCUAGUGUUAGUGUGUACUUUUGGAUUUUUGGUUCUUGUAGGGUAUAGAAAUAUUUUCCUUUGUCUUGUAUUCUGUUGUUUUGAAUGAAUAAAACACAAUGUUUCACGAUCACUACUUUCAUUUGCCAUGGAGAAAUAGCAGGGAAAAAUUUCUACAGAAUAAAAUUAACUGAUGAAUUACAUGCAGAAAAAAUUCAAAUCAAUGAUACAUUGUAAUUUUUAUCUCAAUGCAAUGUUCUUUGUAUUUUAUUUUAUUAUUAUUUUUUUGAGACGGAGUUUCACUUUUGUUGCCCGGGCUGGAGUGCAAUGGCACAAUCUCGGCUCACCACAACCUCUGCCUCCCGGAUUCAAGUGAUUCUCCUGCCUCAGCCUCCUGAAUAGCUGGGAUUACAGGCAUAUGCCAACAUGCCUGGCUAAUUUUGUAUUUUUAGUGGAGACGGGGUUUCUCCACGUUGGUCAGACUUGUCUUGAACUCUGGACCUCAGGUGAUCCACCUGCCUCAGCCUCCUAAAUUGCUGGGAUUACAGGCAUGAGCGACCACUCCUGGCCUUGUUCUUUGUAUUUUAUAAGUGCAUGUAGUGCAAAGGGUCAAAGGGCUUUACAGGUUUUUUGUUUGUUUGUUUUUGUUUUUCCCGAAACAUAGUAGUCCCUUGCCCUUCCUCAUUUUUGUUACCUUGAGACAACAAAUUUUACUACUUCUAACUCAUUAUUUUAUUUAUGUUCACUUUUCUGAAUAGCAUGCUUAUGACACUAAUACUUUUUUUUUCAAUUUUAGACAUUCAUUAUUCAUUUAGAUGUCUUUCUCUCCCCAAACUCACCACAUAAAAUACUCUUCUCAUGUCUCUUUCAGAAAUAUUUGUAUUAAAAUAUGAUUAUAUCAAUAUUUGGCAUUUAUUUCUUAUGACCUUGCCAGUACUCUUAGUUAAACUACAUGGUAAAAAUGAUUUUGCUUUCCCUCCUACAUAACUUUUUUUCCACCUAGAGCUAAUAAUUGUCAUUCUGGGGACUGACUUUUUCUGUAUUUACCAUAAAUUGACCUGAAACUCCCCUGUGAUGCAGCAGGAAUUCUACCAACGUCAACUUCCUUAGAAAGACUCCAUUAGAAGCUUGACUUGGGGCUAGAAGGAGAGGCACACAACUGCCAUCCUGGUGUCUCCCUUCAUCCAGAAAAAGGGGGAGGAAUACAUGAAACCUAGAAUCCACUCUAAAACAUUUUCCAGAACAAAAGGACAUGUGUUUCCGUGUUGUAAAUGUUUAACGAGUGCCCAUAACAAGGAAUAAUAAGUCUAUUAUGUUUGCUUUUGUGUCUGUAAAAGUUGGGGGUAUUGGUUGUAAGCACGAAAACAGAUACUGACUGUUGAAGAAAAAAAAAAAUACGAGGUCAGGAGUUUGAGACCAACUUGGCCAAUAUGGUGAAACCCUGUCUUAGUAAAAAUAGAAAAAUUAGCCAGGCCUGGUGGCACGCACCUGUAGUCCCAGCUACUUGGGAGGCUGAGGCAGAAGAAUCGCUUGAACCCGGGAGGCAGAGGUUGCAGUGAGCCAAGAUCGCACCACUGCACUCCACCCUGGGCAACAGAGCGAGACUCCGUCUCAAAAAAAAAAAAAAAAAAAAAAAAAAAAAGUUAAGUAUUUGAACAUAGGGGUGGCUCAUAGAAUUCCCAGGACACCCGAUGGAGUAGGCUUGCAAAACACAACAUGUGGCAACUCCAGUGGGAAACGAGGCAGGAAACACUCGUUUCCUGCAGAAAGCAACAAUUUGGGCUUCGAUACCCUCCCUAGAACACAGGGCAGUGAAUCUGAGCAGCAUCAGUACCCCACGUUCGGAUGAGUCCUGAGCCCCUAUUUUUAUUCACUGACUUAUUCCAAAAUCAGUGUCUCUUAAAUAUAUCUGGAAGGCAGCAGCUUGUAUCUCCCCCUUCAGCUUCCAUAGUGGCAGUCAGGGUACAACUUACUUUCCAAACAGAACACACUGCGACAUUCCCUCCAGGCUCGUUGAAGAACUUCAACUGACAAAUGUCCCUCCUCGACCAGAUGAUAGUUUUCUUAAAGGCAGGGUUUAAUAUACCCUUUUAUAAAUGUUUCAAGGCCCUGUGUAAUACCUGAGUUUAUUCCAGAUGUAACUAAAUAUAUCCAAGAUUGUUUUAAAAUAAAUUGCUGAAAAAACAAAUAAAUACAGUUAGUAUCUAUAUCAAUAUUCUCAGUUGGCAGUUUUGCAAUAAUGGCCGAUAGUUCAUUUUUAGUAACACUAUUGACAUUGCAUUUGGAUAUUAGGGUUUACUAAUCAUCCGCAUGUAUACAUUGCAUAUUUUUCUAGACUUUAACUUUAUUCAAAUCUAUUGAUUUUUAAACCUGCAACUUAUGUCUAGACACAGGUAUACCUUUACAAGAACUACCAUUUUUUUUGGUAACAUACUACCUCCAAAAUUUCAAGUAAGAAGUUGAUUUUUGUCCAUUUUUAAAUGGAAAACUUGUAAUCAAAAUGCCACAAAAUUAUACUGUGUAUCAUUUGACCUAUAGAAACCAAUAUUAUUACAGGAAGAAAGCAGAGCCAAUCUUCUACCUGUGGUCAAAUAAGUGGAGGCCCUUUCUAGACUAAGUUCUCAUGAGUUUAAAAUACCAAGCAUAAGUUCUCCAAAUUCCUGAAAAGGAAGCCUUGUGUUGUAUUGCCCAGCCAUAUUUGUAAGACAUAAAAAUAAAACUUGAGAAGAAGCUAUGAUAACUUACUUUCUUCAUUCUUCAAAAUUUACAUAAUCUCAACUGAUUUUAUGUUUUUAUGAAAAUGCAUUCUUAAGAUAUAUCCUUAUUCAAUCAUGUAUUCAUUACAUCCUUUAUGCCAGGUAUCCAAAAGUACUUACAGUGACUAAGACCAUUAUUCUUUGAUCAGCUGCCUGAGUAAGACUUUGAGCUCUCCAAUAUACUCUCAGUGAUACUAAGUUUUCUGAGUAACAGCUUUGGAUGUGGCUUCAGUUGAGCUGAUUUAUCCCACACUUUAUUUUUAUCGUAUAAUGGUCCUCAGAAGCAAAUUUUGAUUUUAGCUCACAUAAAAAAUGUACAAAGAAAUGUAAUGGCUCAGUAGCUUCUAGAGAUAGAGAUUACUCUUCUAACCUUUCUGUAAUUUUGUAUGUCUAUUUUAUAAUUCUUUCAAUGUCUAAUGAAUAGCUAUCUUUUUUUGAGACGGAGUCUCGCUCUGUCGCCCAGGCUGGAGUGCAGUGGUGCGACCUCGGCUCACCGCAAGCUGCGUCUUCCAGGUUCACGCCAUUCUCCUGCCUCAGCCUCCCGAGUAGCUGGGACUUCAGGCGCCCACCACCAUGCCCAGCUAAUUUUUUUGUAUUUUUAGUAGAGACGGGGUUUCACCGUGUUAGCCAGGGUGGUCUCGAUCUCCUGACCUCGUGAUCCGCCCGCCUCGGCCUCCCAACGUGCUGGGAUUACAGGAGUGAGCCACCGCGCCCGGCCUCCUUAGUUUCUUAAGGUGGAAGCCUAGAUUAUUGAUUUUAUAUGUUGUUUUCUUUUCCAAUAGUGGCACUUAAUGCUAUAAAUUUCACUUUGUUCCACAAGUUUUGGUAAGCUCUAUUUUUAUUUUCAUUUAGUCCAAAAUAUUUUAAAAUUUCUUUUGAUAUUUCUUCUUUGAGCCAUGAAUUAUUUACAAUGUGUUGUUUAAUCUCUAUAUAUUUUGGGAUUUUUCUACUUUAUAUCUCUUACAGAUUUCUAACUUAAUUUCAUCAUGUUUUAAAAACAUUCUUUGUAUAAUUUCUAUUCUUUUAAAUUUUUCAGGUGUAUUUUAUGGCCCAGAAUAUGGUCUAUCUUGUAGAAUGUUUCAUGUGAUCUUAAGAAGAAUGUUCAUUCUGCUGUUGAGUGUAAUAUUCUACAAAUGUCCAUUAGAUUAAACUGAUUGAUACCACCGUUCAGAUUAUCUAUAUCCUUUCUGAUUUUCCCUCUUCUUGAUCUAUCACAUACUGACAGAUCAAGUGAUCAAGUCUCGUUAAAGACUGCAAGUAAAAUAGUGGAUUUUUCUAUUUCUCCUUGCAGUUUUGUUAGUUUUUGUCUCAUGUAUCUUGAUACUCUUGUUAGUACAUAUACUUUCAGAAUCGUUAGGUUUUCUUGGAGAAUUGACCCCUUUACCACAUGUAAUGUCCCUUUUAUUCUUGAUAAUCUUUCUUGUUCUGUCUGCUUUUUCUGAUAUUAACAUAACUUUCAGUUUUUUAAAAAAUUAACAUUAGCAUCUCACAUCUUUAUCCUUUUAAUUUUAAAUUAUCUAAAUAUUUAUAUUUAAUGUGCCUUUCUUAUAGACAAUGUAUAGUUGCGUCUAUUUGUAAUUUCCCCACUUUUCUUACUUAAAAAUGUUGUAGAUAUAUAGGAGUUGUAUAUAUUUGGGGGGUACAUGUGAUGUUUUGAUACCUGUAUACAAUAUGUAAUGAUCAUAUUGGGUAAUCGUGAUAUCUGUCACCUCUAACAUUCAUCUUUUUUGUGUGUUUAAACCCACCACUUCUAAUUGGUACAUUUAGAUUAUUCAAAUUUAAGUGAUUAUUGAUAUAGUUGGAUUAAUAUCUACUAUGUUUGUAACUUUUCUAUCCUUGCACUCGUUCUUUCUUUUUUAUCCUCCUUUUUCUGUGUUCUCUGAUUUUAACUGGGGUUUUUACAUGAUUUAAUUUUCUCUCGUGGCAUAUCUUUCAUUGAUCAACCUAGGUUUUUCUCCUUUUCCCCUCUUUUUUUUGGUAUUUAUUCUAUUUAGUGUUAUCUGAGCUACCUGAGUUGGUGUCUAUCACUAAUUUUGGCAAGUUCCCAGACGUUAUUACUUCUAACAUUCUUUUGCUCCAUUCUUUCUUCUUCUUCAAUUAUUCCAUAGUCUUGAAUAUUCUGGGUUUUUCCCACUCUUUGAAUUUUAGUUUGAAAAGUUUCUAUUGGCCUAGCUUCAAAGUCAUUCAUUCUUCCUUCGGGGUUCCAAGUCAACUGAUAAUUGCAUCAAAGAUAUCCUUCCUUUCUAUUACUAUGUUUUUUAUUGCUACCAUUUCUUUUUUAUUCCUUCUUAGUGUUUCCAUCUUUCUUCUUACAUUAUCCAUCUGUUGUCUAUUUUUUUCAUGAGAGCUCUUAACAUAUUAAUGAUAAGUUCCAUGUCUGAUAAUUCUGACACGUGUCAUGUCUCUAUCUGGUUCCAAUGAUUGCUUUAUCUCUUCAGACCAUGACUUUUCUUGCCUUUUGACGUUCUUUGACAUUUUUUUUGAAUUUUUUGUUGCAAGCCAGAUCUGGUGUGUUAUGUAAUAGGAACAGGUAAAUAAGUCUUUAGCUUGCAGACUUAUCUUAAUCUGACUAACUAUUAGACUGUGUUUAAAGUCUGUUAUAACCAUAGGUGCUAAAUUUCUUCAAAUUCCUCUAGUGUCUUUGUUUUGUUUGUUCAUGUGUUUUUCCCCUUCUUGAGUUCAGGCUUCCCUAAGUGCUCCUCUUCAGAGAGACUUUCUGUCUUUCAGCUCUUUCCUCUGCAAUUCACUGUUACUAUACUGGAGCCCUGUUGGUGUAGUACUAAGCUGUGGGAAAGGAGAGUGCUCUGUAAUCUUACAGUGAAAUCUCAGUCUUUUAGUGGGUCUGUGUCUGGGACAUUCACAGAGCUUCUCCAGUGGUAUUGCUUCCUCAUCCUCAACUCUCUUUCCUGGCUGCAGCAUUCCCAAUGUAUUUCUUUGAAGGCCUGCCCCCUGUUGACUGUUAUUUUCCCUCUUUCCUUAAGUGGGACAGGGAGACUUCAGGGGCUGGGAUGAGGUUUGGGAAUUGUGCUUGGCAGAGUCCUUUCCAUCUUUGUUACCAAGAAGGUUCAUGGCUUAUUUCUCAAUGGAUGUCCCUCUCUAUCUGUUGCCAGAGCCACGAGGAAAUUUUUCUUGGAUCCUCAUAAUGAGAACCUUGGAGUUUCCUACUGGAAAAGCCCUUGAAUGUGUGGAGUGCCUCAAGAGCACAGCCCCCAUGGGUUUCUUGCUCACACCAGUCCACAAACAGAUGCCAGCAAUUCACCCAACUUACCAUAUAAAGGCUCAUACUAGUUUAUGGCUCCAGUGCUUUGACUCCAGAUAAAUGGCUAUUGGUUGCGUAUCUCUCUGGAUGUAUCUGUAUCUCCAGAUUUUGGGGUGGCAGUUUGCUCAGGACCUUGGUUCUCUAAUAGGUCUAAUAAGAAAAGUCAUUGAUUUUCAGCUUUCCAACUUUCCAGCUUUGUCUUGUUAUAAGCAUGGCAGCAACAUCUUCCAUGCCUUAACAUGAUGACACUAAAGGCAGAAGUCGAUCUCCAUGUAUAAACAUUUUAACACAUAUGUUUUUUGUUAUCGUGGUUUCUGACCUGUCUCUUUGCCCUGACUUUCUGAUACUGCACUAGGGUUCCUGUUGCUGGACUCCAUUCCAUAUGACUUGCUCUCGUCUAGGCUGCUCUUUGGCUCAUCUUUAUAAAUCAUGAUCCAAAAUGAAGCACAUAUUUAUUUUUUAAAUAAAUAUGAAAUGAAGUAUAGACAUCAAACUGAAGAUGAGUAGAUCAUACUGAGUUUCACUGUCUGUGCUUGGAUCAACAUCAGGCCUUAUACAAAUAUUCAAGUCCAGAGGCAAAAGGUAAUAAGGAAAAUUUGUAGCACAAGCCACAAGGAGAUAACAUGUCAAGUCUAUGCGAUUGGAAAUAAACUAAAGAUGAACUGCUGGGGAUGCUCACUCAUCACAGAGCUCAGUCUAAAGCACCAGAUUUCACAAGCAUUUUUUGGGGGAAAUUCUGUUAAAAUGAAAUAUGAGUCACAUGGUGGUGUUUCACUCAUCAUAUGUGUUCAAUAUUAAUUCAUUUUAAGGUUUAGUUGCACAAAAGGUAAAUGAGAAUUAGAAGACUCCAUGGGUAAGAGGAGCCACAGAAGUAAAGCAUUGUCAAGGGUUCUAUGUCUAUAUAUUUAGAUAUUAGGCUUCUGAGAAAAAAACACAAUAGGAAGGAAGAUGAACACAACAGAGGGCAGAAGGUCUAUACGUCCUGAGGCCUUUUAUGCAACGUUUGUUUGUGGAAUGUUUUUUAAGAAUGUGUGAGAGUCAUUUUAAUGUGAAAUAAAGACCUACGUCUACA